ACAGCGGCUUCCUUGAUCCUUGCCACCCGCGACUGAACACCGACAGCAGCAGCCUCACCAUGAAGUUGCUGAUGGUCCUCAUGCUGGCGGCCCUCUCCCAGCACUGCUACGCAGGCUCUGGCUGCCCCUUAUUGGAGAAUGUGAUUUCCAAGACAAUCAAUCCACAAGUGUCUAAGACUGAAUACAAAGAACUUCUUCAAGAGUUCAUAGACGACAAUGCCACUACAAAUGCCAUAGAUGAAUUGAAGGAAUGUUUUCUUAACCAAACGGAUGAAACUCUGAGCAAUGUUGAGGUGUUUAUGCAAUUAAUAUAUGACAGCAGUCUUUGUGAUUUAUUUUAACUUUCUGCAAGACCUUUGGCUCACAGAACUGCAGGGUAUGGUGAGAAACCAACUACGGAUUGCUGCAAACCACACCUUCUCUUUCUUAUGUCUUUUUACUACAAACUACAAGACAAUUGUUGAAACCUGCUAUACAUGUUUAUUUUAAUAAAUUGAUGGCAAAAA